ACGCCGCCGUCGGGCGGUCGUAGGACAUGGCCGCCAGGAGGUAGCUCUCGGUGAUGCCCAGAGCCACGAAGAAGUACAUCUCGGCAAAGCACGCCUGGAAGGAUAUGGCCUGGCCCGGGUGGAGCAGGCCGGCCAGCAGCCUGGGGACCGUGACGGUGGUAAAGCAGACGUCCACGAGGCUCAGACAUGCCACAAAAUGUUGAAUGAAGAUAGGCAGCGUUGGCAAGGAGAGUUUCUGAAACUUCCACUGGAGGGCUCUGCGUGUUCCGGCAGGAAUGGUUUACCAACCCUCUGUGGUUGGAAAUAUUAUUCUGUUUUUACACAUGAAGAAAUGGAAGGCCAGAGUUGCUGAGCAGCUGGUCCUAAGGCACGCCGUCAGUCACUGGAAAAGCAAGUGGCAAGCCUGAGAGUCAGCUCUCUCUGCUCAGAACUCUUGUUCCGAGAGGAAUCUGGGAGAACAACGCUCUGUCUGGAUACUUACUCUAGCCUCAGCACCACCAUUAGAUCCACUGUGGCUUUGUGAAGAUGAAUAAAUUCUCUGGACUUCAUUGGUGUGGAGAGCCAGUUUCUGAGUGCCCCAGAGGAGAAUGCUGUAGUGAACACAGCCCUGUACAGAGAAGACAGCAGCUUGAUUCCUCUCAUUUCUCAGUCAUUAGCCCCUCACUCGCUCUCCGGGAGGAUAACGGGGUGUGCGCAGCUCCUCCCCUUCUUUCCUGAAGAAACCUCAGUGGCUUCCGUGCCCUUGCCAGGGUAUUCUGACCUUUUCAGCUAGCAGAGGAUGAGGAGGACAAGGUGGUGGUGUCAUUGGGCAUGUCAACCAAGAGCAAGAAACUCAUGGAGCCAGAAGCUGGGACCAAUAGGACCGCUGUUGCUGAGUUCAUUCUACUGGGCCUAGUGCAAACAGAAGAGAUGCAGCCAGUUGUCUUUGUGCUCCUCCUCUUUGCCUAUCUGGUCACAACUGGGGGCAACCUCAGCAUCCUGGCAGCCGUCUUGGUGGAGCCCAAACUCCACGCCCCCAUGUACUUCUUCCUGGGGAACCUGUCAGUGCUGGAUGUCGGAUGUAUCACUGUCACUGUUCCUGCAAUGUUGGGUCGUCUCUUGUCCCACAAGUCCACAAUUUCCUAUGACGCCUGCCUCUCCCAGCUCUUCUUCUUCCACCUUCUGGCUGGGAUGGACUGCUUCCUGCUGACCGCCAUGGCCUAUGACCGACUCCUGGCCAUCUGCCAGCCCCUCACCUACAGCACCCGCAUGAGUCAGACAGUCCAGAGGAUGUUGGUGGCUGCGUCCUUGGCUUGUGCCUUCACCAACGCACUGACCCACACUGUGGCCAUGUCCACGCUCAACUUCUGUGGCCCCAAUGAGGUCAAUCACUUCUACUGUGACCUCCCACAGCUCUUCCAGCUCUCCUGCUCCAGCACCCAACUCAAUGAGCUGCUGCUCUUUGCUGUGGGUUUCAUCAUGGCAGGCACACCUUUGGUUCUCAUCAUCACUGCCUACAGCCACGUGGCAGCUGCAGUUCUACGAAUCCGUUCAGUGGAGGGCCGAAAGAAGGCCUUCUCCACGUGUGGCUCCCACCUCACCGUGGUUUGUCUUUUCUUUGGAAGAGGUAUCUUCAACUACAUGAGACUGGGUUCAGAGGAGGCUUCAGACAAGGAUAAAGGGGUUGGAGUUUUCAACACUGUUAUCAACCCUAUGCUGAACCCUCUUAUCUACAGCCUCAGAAACCCUGAUGUUCAGGGUGCUCUGUGGCAAAUAUUUUUGGGGAGGAGAUCACUGACCUGAGAGGUAAUGGGGUCCCUCCUUUCCUGCCUUUUCUGGACUGAGGAAAAUUUCCCAUGAAGACAGUAACCAGGAAAAAUUCAGCCACAACUAUUUUUCCUAUCUCCUGAUGCUUGAAGAUCGGUGUUACAUAUUUGUCCUACUAGGAAACCCUACAUAAUUUAUUCAUUCAACAAAUACUUAUUAGAGUACCUCUAUGAUCUGGACAGUCUUCCAAGGCAUUGGUGGACAAAAUGGACAAAAGUCUCUGCACUCAUGCAACUCACAUGCUAUAAAAGUAGACAAAGUAAAUAAGCAUCAUAUAUACCACAUGAUGAUAGUUUCUAUAGAGAUGAACAAAGAUGUUAAUAUGAAGUCAGGUUCUGCCAAGCAAGCCCUGUGCAAGUUUUACCCUGUUUUUGGCUGUGCCUACUUUCUGGAUAGAGUUAAAGCCUUGUAGUUCUGUGUGCCUGGCAAGCAGCAUUCUACAAAGAAUGUCCAGUCGGUCAAUCACAGCCUAAGUGACCAAAAGUAUUUCUGCAAUAUUUCUGGUGAGGACAUGAGAUUCCCUGCAGAUCAGAAUAGGGGAAAAUUUUUUGUUUGUUUCUUUGUUUUGUUUUGUUGUUGUUUUGUUAAAAACUUGUUAAAAAGUUUUUUAAAAAAACCAAAACCAUAGGCCUAGUGCAAUGGAUUAUUUCAUUCAUUUGUUUGCCUUUCACCUUCAUUUUCUUCUCUCCGCUACCACAAAAGAAUCCUGCUGGAUGUUGACUGGGCGCAGGGUGGCUGACGCCUGUAAUCCCAGCACUUUGGGAGGCCGAGGCGGAUGGAUCACGAGGUCAGGAGAUCGAGACCAUCCUGACUAACAUAGUGAAACCCCUUCUCUACUAUAAAUACAAAAACAAAAUUAGCCGGUGUAGUGGUGGGCGCCUGUAGUCCCAGCUACUCGGGAGGCUGAGGCAGGAGAAUGGCGUGAACCUGGGGGGCGGAGCUUGCAGUGAGCCGAGAUAGCGCCACUGCACUCCAGCCUGGGCGACAGAGCAAGACUCCGUCUCAAAAAAAAAAAAAAAAAGAAUCCUGCUGGAUGUUUAGGGAACAGGAAAGGUCUAGAGAGGAAAAGAGCCCACUAAAUUAAAACUACGUUCAUACAUAUAUGAUAUAUCUUAAGGUCAUAAAAGGAAGGUUUCAUCUCCAUUCCCUGCCAUGCCUUUUUCUCUCAUUUAAUGUUACCUUCCUCACACAUAUGAUAAAGUUUUUGAAAGAGUAAAUGUUUGUAUUACAAUCAGGUCCUUAGAAUUUUCAAUGUAGAAUAUCCAAUAUAACCUUCUCCUCCAAAGUCUUACUUAGCUCUCUCAAAGCUCCUUGCUUAGAAAAUACAUACCCAUAAAUGUAGUUCCUGGAAAGGAGGGAUGCAUGCAUGCCUGUCUUCCUUCCUUCCCAGUGUAAAUAUAUUUAUUUUAAAAAUUAUUCAGAAUGUUAUACCUAAUAGUGGAAACAUUCAGACGAUAUUAUUUUGUCAAGUAGGAAAUAAAAAUCCAAAUGUUCCUUCACUGCACCAAAAAUCACACUGUUCAGAGUUUACGCCUCUGACAAUUGUUGUGUUUUUUCCUCUAGCGAUUUCCUGUAUAUAUGAUAUGCCCGUUUCACAUCAGUAGAACCAUACUGUUCUGUGAUCUGCUUCCUGUUUUUCCUGCAUAUUGUGCCAUACAAUCUUUUACAUAAUGAAGACUAACAUCCUGCUUUAUCUGUUUUAAUGGUGGCACAGUAUAUCAUUAAACAUGUAAGUCACAAUUUCUUUCAUUAAACCUCUAUUUCUAUAAUUUGGGUUAUUUUCAAUUGUUUUGCAACAACAAUGUUGUGAUGAAUAUUCUUUUUUUUUUCUUU